AAGCUGCCUGCUCGCUGAGCUCAGCGCUGACACUCACAGGAGCUGCGUUCGCCGGAUCCUCUGAGAGGCUCUGCAACGAUCCCGAUCCAAUUCAGCAGCGUUUUAAAAGGAAACUCGUGCAGGGCCACUGAAAAGUCAGGGGAGGCUCAGAUGUUAUUUCCCAGGGAUUCCUGUUUUUCCAGAAACGUUGUCACCAAAUAAGUAUGAGACUGUUAAUUUGGAGAAACAAUUAGCCCCUACAAAAAAAAAAAAGAAAGAAAAAAGAAAAAAAAAAGAACCGGAGGGGAGAAGGCUAGGGCGGAAGACAAGGAAGCUGCUGCUUGGAUUCGCUGGUGGAGGAAAGUGCGACCUGGACCUGCGCUUAGGGGCUCCCGUCCCCUUACUUCAGCACCAGAGGGGAUGGACAGCGUCUCCGGACUGAGCUGCAGCCACAGGGACGGAACUACGCUGCCGCCGCCGCUGUCCUUGCCGCCACUGUCGUCGCCACGGGCAGCUGGGCUACUUGCUCCUCGCAGCUAAAAGGCGGUGCCUCCUAUUACCCCCUCGCCUCCCGGCCCCCUUCCUUAAUGGAUGAAAAGUACCCCUCCCUCUACACCUGCUGUACCUAAGGACAGGACUCUGAGGAGUACUCUUGCUCCACAGAUUAAACUCUCAGCAGCAACUUCAAGAAUCAUUUUUCUAUAGGGGUCUGGGAGGAAUUCUGGAGGAGAGUAAAGUCGAAGUUCUUAGAAGCUCUGAGAAAUCAUGGGCCGUGCGGUAGGGGUUGAAAUGCUCAAAGGUCCACACUUCUUGAAAUAAACAGAAUGGUCUUGAGUGGAUUGCAACUGUUUUGGAAAUAGCUUUGUGAAAAGAGGGUGGAGAGCUACUCAAAAUUCUACGUUAGAGAGACUGAAAAGACAUCUAAUUUCAUUGCUCGGCAGCUUAGCAGAGUGAGCACAUAGCAUGUGUUGGAAGAGACAACAUCCUGUGGCAGAAGAUGGAAAGGCGAAGGCUUCAUAGCAAGAGCUGAUCAAAGAUAAAGUUAGAAGGUCAGAAGACAUGCAGACUCUGUAGUGGAGAUGUGGCACCACAAACACUGCUUGGGCGUUAGACGGUCUUCAGUUGGCUUCCCAAGAAAGCUGUUUACUAGAUUUGUGACCAGGGGGAUAUCCUUGGAGCCUCAGUUUUCAUAUCUUCAUAAGGGGAAAUAAUAAUAAUACAGAUGCCUGGAGGAUCAUUUGUGAAUACCUGCAAAAUAUUUCCCACGGGGCCUGUUGCCAACCCAGCUCACAACGGUCCACUCAACCUAAUGGACGUUGGGAUGUUGAAAUGUAGGUCACUCUUUUCUUCAAAGCCCUUUCUGCCUUUCUACAGUAAAGAGAUGCUGGGAUAUGAAAGAGAUUUGAAACAACUAAUUCCCCAACUUAGACUAGAAUGCACUGAAAUAGAGAGAGCGGGGGAGAGAGGGAGAGAGAGAGAGAGAGACAGAAGGAGACAGAAGAAAGGGGGAAGAGGAGAGGAGAGGGAAGAAGAGAACAGGGCUAGAAUGGAAUGAGUUAGUCAGGAGCUAAUUAAUGACCAAAGAUGAAGAAAAGAAAGCAAUGCAAAAAAAUGAAAAUGCAGCCAAGGCAGAGCACAUUGGAUAGGACUAUACUUAACAGAGAAAUGUCUUGCUGUUGUGCAGGCUUCCUCAAUCUAAAAUAGCAUGGGUGGCCUUCAUUCAUGGCCACGAUCACUGAAGUGGCUCUGAAGUGUCUUUGUACCUGUAAAAAUGGGCUUGUUUUGAUUUUUUGAACAUACAAUUAAAAUUGUUGUCUUUAUUGUAAAGGCCCAUGUUUCAUUUAAUAGUCUACCAGAAGUAUGAGGACAUCACUUAAAAACACUUAAAUUAGAAUGAAAUAGUAAUACAAAUAAAAAUAAGAAAAACAGCCAUUUUAUUGAGAGUUUAGCUGAGUUGGGCAGUUACUUGUUUCCCUCAUUAUCUAAUGUUGAAUUCCAGGUAGCAGGUUCUAUAUUUCUGUUCAUUUUAGAAAUGAGGAAAUGGAUGUUUAAGAAGUUGAGUAACAUCCGAAAUAUCCUCCAAUUAUUAGCUGACUUCGGGAUUCAGUCCUGGGUCUGCCUGACCCUAGACGUCAGUGUCACUAACCACUAUGUUAGGAAGAAAAUAUAGGAGAUAUGGAUGAAUAAAGGUAAUCUUCUUCCACACUUGGGUAAAAUCACAAGCUUGGGAGAAUUGACACCAUAAUGUAGGAAUUCUUCCUUGGACAAGCUGAAAAUCAUUCUAUUUCGGUACAUUAAAAGCCUUCACGCUGUUAAGAUUUUGGAGAAGAAUGAGCGAAUUUGGUAGUGUAACUAGCAGGCGGGGAAGGACUGUCCCUUAUGGCUUAGCAAUGAGCAGCAGGGCAGUUCACAAUGGCGAGACGCAGACGCCUUUGGGGCGGUGCAGCCAGAGCGGAGUGCGCCUGGGACUGAGUGUCCUCCUCGGGGACUGCAUGGGCCCCGCACCGCCGCCUGCCCCGCGCCACGACAGCCCAGAGCACGGAUGGGCCCAGACUGUCCUACAGCCGUUUCAGCAGGCGAGGGUCUGUCCAGCAGCACCUAAACAGCUUUUGUAUGUCCUGUCUCCAAAGUGUGUGGCUUUAAGUCAGGUUCUGUGCUUUUGAUGACAAUAUUUUCUUUGGGUCGGGAUCAUUUUCAUCUGUUGCCCCUUCUGCCCAACCUUUGCACUUCCCCCCGAUCCUCCUCACCCCUUCCCUUCCUCUGCCUGUCUGCACACCAACGUCCUUGGGCUCCCUCAUUCUCCAGUUCUUGGCUUGGUCUGACUGGGGACUUCUCACACCUAGCUUGUCGUCGCGCUCUAGGGCCAUUGCAUCUUGGUUAAAAGGCCUGUCUCUGCAGACUGAAGGCUCUCUGCGGGCAGGACCAGGCCAGUUUGGCUUCUCCCUGCCCGCCCUCGGAGCCUGCUCCAGGUAUACUGGCUGAAUGUUCUGAGAGACCCGCAGCCCAGGAUUGCUGAGUCGCUUGUGUGUCCGCUGUUUACAGCUGUGCGUGCGUGUGUGUGCAGGGAAACAGCCAGGCAGAUGCACAUGGUUAUUUAUAUCUUCAGAUUAUUUCUGUGAGGAAAAUUCUAUCCUGGUGAAAGAGCUUGCUGUUGAAAAACAGUAACUGUACCCAUAUAGACACCACAGUAUUCGCUCAAUGUAUUUGACAGACACACUCAUAUUGUCAGGGUAAAAGGAGGCAGCAGCUUCUUUGAAAUGCAGGGACAGAGCAAGUGACAAGGAAAAAACCACACAGCAGGUAUGUCCACAUUGUUGUGCAACCAAUCUCCAGAGCUCUUUGAUCUUGCAAAACUGAGACAGCGUACCUAUUACACAUCAAACUCCUCGUUCCCAGUUCUCCUCCAGCGCCUGGCAGCCACUAUUCUACUUUCUUUCUCUAUGAAUUACAUUACUCUGGAUAUCUCUUCCAAUUUUUAUUAUAGCCUGCUUGACGUUGUAAAGAAAUCAAAUGUUUGGCCCAGUAGCCAUUCUCCUCUCUGCUUGCUCCAUCACGCUGAAAAUCAACUGGUAGCUUCAGCUGUAGCAGACGGAGCCCUGAGCUCUCCUGACUUGUACAUGCGCUUACUGCUCUCCAGAAUGUUGAGAUUGCCCGAGAAGUGACCCCAGCAAAAGAAAAAUAUUGCUGUACCUAAAUUCAAACGACAUCCUUUGUGGUGCCACAGCACAUGGAUUUCAGAACCGCCUGUGAGGAGACAAAGACAGGAAUUUGUUUGCUGCAGGAUGGUAACCAGGAGCCUUUCAAAGUGCGGCUGCACCUAGCCAAAGACAUUUUGAUGAUCCAGGAACAGGAUGUGAUAUGUGUGUCUGGUGAGCCUUUCUAUUCUGGUGAAAGAACGGUGACCAUCAGAAGACAAACAGUAGGAGGAUUUGGAUUAAGCAUAAAGGGAGGAGCAGAACAUAACAUUCCAGUUGUCGUUUCAAAAAUCUCCAAGGAACAAAGAGCGGAACUUUCAGGACUACUUUUUAUUGGAGAUGCAAUUCUACAGAUAAAUGGCAUUAAUGUGAGAAAAUGUAGACAUGAAGAAGUGGUUCAGGUUCUUCGGAAUGCUGGAGAAGAAGUGACUCUAACAGUGUCAUUUUUAAAAAGAGCACCUGCUUUCCUCAAACUCCCAUUGAAUGAAGAUUGUGCAUGUGCUCCAAGUGACCAGAGCAGUGGCACCUCCUCUCCUCUCUGUGACAGUGGCUUACAUCUCAACUACCAUCCCAACAAUACAGACACAUUAUCAUGCUCGUCGUGGCCGACGUCUCCAGGCUUGAGGUGGGAGAAGCGAUGGUGCGACCUCAGACUGAUCCCUCUACUUCAUUCGCGCUUCUCUCAGUAUGUGCCCGGCACAGAUUUGAGUCGGCAGAAUGCCUUUCAAGUCAUUGCUGUGGAUGGGGUCUGCACUGGGAUUAUUCAGUGCCUCUCUGCUGAAGACUGCGUUGACUGGCUACAAGCAAUAGCAACUAACAUUUCAAAUCUCACAAAGCACAAUAUUAAAAAAAUCAACAGAAACUUUCCUGUAAACCAGCAGAUUGUCUACAUGGGCUGGUGUGAAGCCCGGGAGCAAGACCCCCUCCAGGACAGAGUGUACUCCCCGACCUUCCUGGCCCUGAGGGGCUCAUGUCUCUACAAGUUUCUGGCACCUCCAGUGACCACCUGGGACUGGACGAGAGCAGAGAAAACAUUCUCAGUUUAUGAGAUUAUGUGCAAGAUCCUCAAGGACAGUGACCUGCUGGACCGACGGAAACAGUGCUUCACCGUGCAGUCUGAGUCUGGGGAGGACCUGUACUUCUCAGUGGAGCUGGAAAGUGACCUCGCCCAGUGGGAAAGAGCCUUCCAGACAGCAACCUUUCUAGAAGUAGAACGGAUACAGUGCAAGACCUAUGCAUGUGUGCUAGAAAGUCAUCUAAUGGGACUCACAAUUGAUUUCAGCACAGGAUUUAUCUGCUUUGAUGCUGCAACAAAGGCUGUCCUUUGGAGGUAUAAAUUCUCUCAGCUUAAAGGUUCUUCAGAUGAUGGCAAGAGCAAAAUCAAAUUUUUGUUUCAGAAUCCAGAUACUAAACAGAUUGAAGCAAAGGAGUUGGAAUUUUCUAAUUUAUUUGCUGUUCUUCACUGCAUUCAUUCCUUCUUUGCUGCCAAGGUAGCUUGUUUGGACCCUCUAUUUUUAGGCAAUCAAGCUACUGCUUCUACUGCUGCCAGCUCUGCUACCACGAGCAAAGCAAAGUAUACAACUUGACAUACUGAACUCUUCAUUGACACACCCCAUGACUGUAUAAGCAGGACACAUUUACUCAUCAUUUUAGACCCUAGAGAAACCAUAACAUCACCAAGUCGACAGUGGAGGCAAAUCAAAAUUUCGGCAGAAAAAGAAGGUCAUGUGGAACCUCAAAAACACUUCUAUUCUGGAUGACAUCUGUGAAAUAUACUACAUGAACAGAACAGCUUGUUCUCACUCAGUUGCUUUGUACCAGUAAGUGUAUUGCUUUCACCAAAAGUGGAGACAAAAGAAUAAAUUAUUUGAAGAAGUAUGUAAAUAACAUAAAAAUAGUAAGCUACCUAUGAAUAAAAAUACUUAUUAAAUGAUUACUUCUGUAUUUUAGAUUAUUUUGUAUGACUAGUACAUGUUGGGCAGAGUCAUAGGAAAACAAAUGCCCUAUCUUGUAUUAUGAGGGACAUAAAAGAGUUAAAAACCAUAAAUCAGCAAGGAGCAUGCAAAAAAAUCUCAUCAAAGAAGGAUGCACUUUAAUUUGCUGAUGUAAAUUUGCCCUUGUGUUCUCAUCCCAUGAUUUGACACUGGCAUUCCAAUUGUUUUUAUCUUAUUGUAAAUAUUCCGAAGAACUUCCAAAGGAUAAUUACAUUGACCCAUGAUAGAUACAAUGUGAAAUGGACUAUUCUCCCUUGGAUCACUGUUAUUGAAAUGUCUUAUUAGCUGCCAAAGUCAAUCAAAUAUGCCAACAGUGUAUUAAUUUAAUUAUGAGUGAUGGAAAAUUUCAUGAACCUCUCAUUUCUUCCUUGGUUUGAAAGAGAUUUGUAUUUUACCUAAUAAGAUUUAUUAUCAAAUUAAAGUUUCAUAAAUUUUCAGUGAACCCAAAACCUUUUGUAGAGAAAAUAAUAUAAACAAAUAUGGUGUGAGAAACAAUUCUUUGUAAUCCGAAGUCUACUAGUUAAUCAUGAACUAAAAUGUCCCCCGAAAACAGUCCCAAAGCUAUUAUAGAUGUUAAUUAAAUGACAUUUUUUCAUUUUAGUACUAUUUUAUGAGAAACAAAGGUGAUAUUUAAAGAUAAAAGUUAAAAUUCUUUAACCUCCCUUGUCAUGGAAAGUGAUUAAGUAAUGCCAACUAUGCAGGUUGUUUUAGGUAUUUUGUCCUAAGAAUGUAAAUGUGAAAGGCUGGGAAAUUUGAAAGCCUUAGAGGUGUGCAAUUUACUCAGAUUCCAGGUAUUAUUCAACUAGUUGUAUAACAUGGAACACAGUCUCUGUCCUUCAGUACAGCUUUUUUGAGAUAUUUUAAAAAGUCAGCUGUGUAUGUAAAAAAAAAAAAAAAUUUUUAUUGAUACACAUGCUCCCAGGUAAACCAAGUAUUAUGUGUGUCCUUGUGGAGAUAACCAAGUAUCUAAUAAAUUGAUUCAAUUUUUUUUUUCAAAUAUGUUUUUAAAAAUCACUCAAGAAGGAAACAAAGUGAUUUCUAUAAAGGACAGAUUUACUAAUUUAAAAAAUUAAUAUCAAGUUGUUUUUAUACUCAUGAUUCAUUAAUUUAUUUUGCAUCAGAUUAAUUUGUAAAUACAUCAAAUUGAAAAGAAAAAGUGAGGGUUUAUAAUUGUCCCUGGGAAAAUGUUAAACUGAAUCUAACAUACCUUACCCAAAGAACUGUGGCAAAUUACAAUAAACAGUUUCAGUGUAAUGUAUUUUGACCGUAAAACUAAGUACACAUUUGUAAUUAGGAUAGAACUUUAGAAUUAUUGCACACUAUAUUGAUCAAAUACAACAGUCAUUGUAAAAUUGAAACCCACCAAAAGCAGCCUUCAGUAGUAGGCCACUUCUGAACUUAUGGAGAAAAAGCAGUGGGAUACAUCGAACUUAGAAUUUUCAGCUGUGGCAAGUGGUUCAUUAUGGAACUUCUGCUUCCAACCAGAGCUGAAUCUCAGUGUGCCCCAUAUUGGGGUUACAUGAAUGUGUCCACAAUCUGGAAGGCAAUAUGACAUGGGCUAAUUAUCCAUAAGCAAAAGAAAAACGUUUCAACAGUUUACCUACCUGUAAUAGAAUGAUUUAAAAAUUGUGAAAUUUUGUAAACGUUCCAUUUUAGAAUUUAAAAAACCUAUUAACCAUUAGCUAUCUUUUUAGUGUUAUUAUGAAAAUUUAGCCUAUGCUCAUGUGUGUUACGAAGGAAAAGGUGCACAAUGAGAUAUGUAUAAAUAUAUAUCUCCUCAGAGAAUACACACACACCUACAUAUGUAUUUAUAUGCAUACAUGGGUGUAUAUAUAUAUAAAUAUAAUGAAAUGCUGACCAUUAAUUAUAUUAGAAGAAUGUUUUGUGUACAUACAUUUAAUAUACUUUAAAUUACGUUGUAAAAUGUAGCUUGAUUAAAAACUUAUGACAAUACCAUUAUGAAUAUUUUUGAUACUAUUGAUAAAAAACAUAAGCCGUGAUUUUUAUUUAACAUGAUUAGUACAACAGCCAAAAAGUAACAAAAUACUAUUCUCGUUUUCAUCAGUUUAACAAUUAGUAUUUAAUGUUUUCUUUACAAUGUGGUGAUUAGUCAUUGGCAUUUGUUAUAACUUGGACUACUUGAAUGAGAAAGCUUUGAAAUGAACAAAAACACUUAAAAAUUUCUAUCUCUCAUAUAAUUUAGGUUUACAUGUAAGAGAUUUAUUCAUAAAAUCCUAGUUUGUACAUUAAGCACAUUUUAACAGCAAAAUGCUAAUGUGUUAACCCCUCCAGUGCCUUGGUAUGUGUGAGCGUGUAUGUGUGUUUGGGUGUGUGUCUGUGUAUGUGUGUGAGUGUGUAAGUGUUAUCAUUAAAGGGUUCAUUACAGUGUACAUAACACAAGCUUAAUGGAGAAUAUUGUAGGUAUUUAGGUCAGAGAAUGAAGUUCAAAGUCAUUUGAAAACUGCUAACUACUAUAAUAAUGUCUUUUGCCUGAUAAAGAAUAACAAUUCAUCUAAGUCGAAGUAUAUUACAGAAAGGGCAUUUAUAAUUUGUUAAAAUGCAACAAGUAUUUAUUUAAAAAAUAGUUUAAUAGAUAGUGUAAGUGUAAUGUAUAUCUGAACACUUAUCCAGCUUUUUUAAAAUGGGAGGAUAAUCAGGUAAUUAUUUCUUGCCCAUAUUUCAGGCAUGUACCAACUUAUAAUUUUGAAAUCUUCGCUCAUAAAGCUGUCAUUCAGCAAGAAAAAGAAAGCAAUUACUUGAAAAUAAAUGUCAAGUCCAUAUUAGCCAUGCAAAGAGAGAAAUUUUCCUUUGGGUGCAUUAGUUUAUAGAUCAACAUUUCCCUCAUUUACAGUGCUGAAGCUUGAUCAUGAACUUUGUCUAUGUUGAAUGCUGGAUUUAAGAAAAGCUUGAUUUAUUACUGAGAAAAAUUAAUAAUCCUAACGAUAAUUUAGAAUUACUGCUAGAAAUCAGCAGUGUGGAGAAGCUUUAAAAGCACAAGGAUGAUCUUGUGCUUAACUUUUUAAGGUAAGUGUAGAUGUUCGGAUACUAAUAACAAAGAUUUUGCUACUAUUAAUAUUGCUGUGCUCAUAAUUUCUCCUUAUGAAAUUGCUUUAUUCAUACUUCUAAAAUUGUUCUUUAUUGUUUAUUCUUACUACCGAAUACUUUAAAAUCAUAAUGCCACUUAUUUGCACAUUUGAAUUUGCUUUUGAAAAUAAAAUAUUAUAAAUGUUAUAUAUUUUAUACAUGUUAAAAUGCAGUGAAAAGACAAGAAAUAUAAAAUGUAAAUAUAUUUAUUUCAUUUUUAAUUGUUUUGGUGGAUGUUUGUAAAAUGUAAAUUAAUAUCUGUGACAAAAAUUUGUCACUUCAUUCUUUCAGUUCAUUAAUGUACUACUAAUGAAACCAUACUUUUUUAAAUGAAGCAUACUGGAAAAUAAAAACAAAUACUUUUUACUAGA